CAUUGGCGUCUUGGGGCUGUUACACACACGCGCGCUGUCCAUUGCAGCUUACAUAAAGGCGGGCGCGAUUAUGCAAUUAUAUUGUUAGCGAUAUUUCAAGAGCAAUGGCUCGUUUUCUUAGGAUUUCAACACGAAGGCAUCAUGCAUUUUUGAAAAACUAGUAUUGAGAAUAAUACCUUGCAACGUAAAGAAUGUUUUUUGGUAUUUUUACACAAUCUCUACUUUGACCAAACGAGUCUGGACAGUUUUCUUUUAAUGGAAAAUAGGAGAAAUGGAGGAAAGAAUGGAAAUGAUUUCUGAAAGGCCAAAAGAGAGUAUGUAUUCCUGGAACAAAACUGCAGAGAAAAGUGAUUUUGAAGCUGUAGAAGCACUUAUGUCAAUGAGCUGCAGUUGGAAGUCUGAUUUUAAGAAAUACGUUGAAAACAGACCUGUUACACCAGUAUCUGAUUUGUCAGAGGAAGAGAAUCUGCUUCCGGGAACACCUGAUUUUCAUACAAUCCCAGCAUUUUGUUUGACUCCACCUUACAGUCCUUCUGACUUUGAACCCUCUCAAGUGUCAAAUCUGAUGGCACCAGCGCCAUCUACUGUACACUUCAAGUCACUCUCAGAUACUGCCAAACCUCACAUUGCCGCACCUUUCAAAGAGGAAGAAAAGAGCCCAGUAUCUGCCCCCAAACUCCCCAAAGCUCAGGCAACAAGUGUGAUUCGUCAUACAGCUGAUGCCCAGCUAUGUAACCACCAGACCUGCCCAAUGAAAGCAGCCAGCAUCCUCAACUAUCAGAACAAUUCUUUUAGAAGAAGAACCCACCUAAAUGUUGAGGCUGCAAGAAAGAACAUACCAUGUGCCGCUGUGUCACCAAACAGAUCCAAAUGUGAGAGAAACACAGUGGCAGAUGUUGAUGAGAAAGCAAGUGCUGCACUUUAUGACUUUUCUGUGCCUUCCUCAGAGACGGUCAUCUGCAGGUCUCAGCCAGCCCCUGUGUCCCCACAACAGAAGUCAGUGUUGGUCUCUCCACCUGCAGUAUCUGCAGGGGGAGUGCCACCUAUGCCGGUCAUCUGCCAGAUGGUUCCCCUUCCUGCCAACAACCCUGUUGUGACAACAGUCGUUCCCAGCACUCCUCCCAGCCAGCCACCAGCCGUUUGCCCCCCUGUUGUGUUCAUGGGCACACAAGUCCCCAAAGGCGCUGUCAUGUUUGUGGUACCCCAGCCCGUUGUGCAGAGUUCAAAGCCUCCGGUGGUGAGCCCGAAUGGCACCAGACUCUCUCCCAUUGCCCCUGCUCCUGGGUUUUCCCCUUCAGCAGCAAAAGUCACUCCUCAGAUUGAUUCAUCAAGGAUAAGGAGUCACAUCUGUAGCCACCCAGGAUGUGGCAAGACAUACUUUAAAAGUUCCCAUCUGAAGGCCCACACGAGGACGCACACAGGAGAAAAGCCUUUCAGCUGUAGCUGGAAAGGUUGUGAAAGGAGGUUUGCCCGUUCUGAUGAACUGUCCAGACACAGGCGAACCCACACGGGUGAGAAGAAAUUUGCGUGCCCCAUGUGUGACCGGCGGUUCAUGAGGAGUGACCAUUUGACCAAGCAUGCCCGGCGCCAUCUAUCAGCCAAGAAGCUACCAAACUGGCAGAUGGAAGUGAGCAAGCUAAAUGACAUUGCUCUACCUCCAACCCCUGCUCCCACACAGUGACAGACCGGAAAGUGAAGAGUCAGAACUAACUUUGGUCUCAGCGGGAGCCAGUGGUGAUGUAAAAAUGCUUCCACUGCAAGUCUGUGGCCCCACAACGUGGGCUUAAAGCAGAAGCCCCACAGCCUGGCACGAAGGCCCCGCCUGGGUUAGGUGACUAAAAGGGCUUCGGCCACAGGCAGGUCACAGAAAGGCAGGUUUCAUUUCUUAUCACAUAAGAGAGAUGAGAAAGCUUUUAUUCCUUUGAAUAUUUUUUGAAGGUUUCAGAUGAGGUCAACACAGGUAGCACAGAUUUUGAAUCUGUGUGCAUAUUUGUUACUUUACUUUUGCUGUUUAUACUUGAGACCAACUUUUCAAUGUGAUUCUUCUAAAGCACUGGUUUCAAGAAUAUGGAGGCUGGAAGGAAAUAAACAUUACGGUACAGACAUGGAGAUGUAAAAUGAGUUUGUAUUAUUACAAAUAUUGUCAUCUUUUUCUAGAGUUAUCUUCUUUAUUAUUCCUAGUCUUUCCAGUCAACAUCGUGGAUGUAGUGAUUAAAUAUAUCUAGAACUAUCAUUUUUACACUAUUGUGAAUAUUUGGAAUUGAACGACUGUAUAUUGCUAAGAGGGCCCAAAGAAUUGGAAUCCUCCUUAAUUUAAUUGCUUUGAAGCAUAGCUACAAUUUGUUUUUGCAUUUUUGUUUUGAAAGUUUAACAAAUGACUGUAUCUAGGCAUUUCAUUAUGCUUUGAACUUUAGUUUGCCUGCAGUUUCUUGUGUAGAUUUGAAAAUUGUAUACCAAUGUGUUUUCUGUAGACUCUAAGAUACACUGCACUUUGUUUAGAAAAAAAACUGAAGAUGAAAUAUAUAUUGUAAAGAAGGGAUAUUAAGAAUCUUAGAUAACUUCUUGAAAAAGAUGGCUUAUGUCAUCAGUAAAGUACCUUUAUGUUAUGAGGAUAUAAUGUGUGCUUUAUUGAAUUAGAAAAUUAGUGACCAUUAUUCACAGGUGGACAAAUGUUGAUGUUGUCCUGUUAAUUUAUAGGCGUUUUUUGGGGAUGUGGAGGUAGUUGGGUAGAAAAAUUAUUAGAACAUUCACUUUUGUUAACAGUAUUUCUCUUUUAUUCUGUUAUAUAGUGGAUGAUAUACACAGUGGCAAAACAAAAGUACAUUGCUUAAAAUAUAUAGUGAAAAAUGUCACUAUAUCUUCCCAUUUAACAUUGUUUUUGUAUAUUGGGUGUAGAUUUCUGACAUCAAAACUUGGACCCUUGGAAAACAAAAGUUUUAAUUAAAAAAAAUCCUUGUGACUUACAAUUUGCACAAUAUUUCUUUUGUUGUACUUUAUAUCUUGUUUACAAUAAAGAAUUCCCUUUGGUA